AGCGUGCUGAAGCCGGAGCGAGCUAGCCGCCCGGAGCCGCGCCGACCCAGCUGAGCCCAGCCCACGGGACGCCAGACCUCGACCGUCGCUCCUACCCCGGCCACCGCUCGGAGCCGAGGCGGACGCGUCCCGAUCUUCCCCUGUCCCCACCCUGCCCCGACCCUCCUCUCCACCUCUCGCGUCGUGACACCAGCUGGUAAAUACUCCGCUGUUCGUCCCUCAAACCCUCGGCAGCCAGCCGUGGGCGUGAGGGAGGGUUCUCUCUCCUCUCGAUGGGGGUGUUGCAAACACAGCGGGGAGCCCCCUGGUAAGGGUCCCCGGUAAACGGGGGAGUCGCAGCUUUUUCUCUUGCUGCUGAAGUCGCCCACGCACCAUCCGGGGAGUCCUACGGGGAGGGAGCAGAGAUUUUUUUUUCCCCCAUAUUGCUGCUGCUUAGUACGUGGGCGAUGGCAGUGAGAUGGCUCAGGGAAGGGGCCGAGGAGGCCCUGGGUAAGCGAGGGCUUCGGGGGUUAUUUUCCCAUUUACACGGCUCCAGAGAUCGGCACAACAUCUUCCUCCUUUGCUCCUAAACGUUCCUCUUCUGGUCUCCGGCAGCCUCUUGGUCAUGAAAGCCCUCAGAUUGUCGGCUUCCGCCCUCUUCUGCCUUCUGCUGAUCAACGGGUUAGGGGCAGCACCCCCUGGUCGCCCUGAGGCGCAGCCUCCUCCUCUCAGCUCUGAGCAUAAAGAGCCGGUAGCCGGGGACGCAGUGCCCGGGCCAAAGGAUGGCAGCGCCCCAGAGGUCCGAGGCGCUCGGAAUUCCGAGCCGCAGGACGAGGGAGAGCUUUUCCAGGGCGUGGAUCCCCGGGCGCUGGCCGCGGUGCUGCUGCAGGCACUCGACCGUCCCGCCUCACCCCCGGCACCAAGCGGCUCCCAGCAGGGGCCGGAGGAAGAAGCAGCUGAAGCUCUGCUGACCGAGACCGUGCGCAGCCAGACCCACAGCCUCCCGGCGCCGGAGAGCCCGGAGCCCGCGGCUCCGCCUCGCCCUCAGACUCCGGAGAAUGGGCCCGAGGCGAGCGAUCCCUCCGAGGAGCUCGAGGCGCUAGCGUCCCUGCUCCAGGAACUGCGAGAUUUCAGUCCAAGUAGCGCCAAGCGCCAGCAGGAGACGGCGGCAGCAGAGACGGAAACCCGCACGCACACGCUGACCCGAGUGAAUCUGGAGAGCCCGGGGCCAGAGCGCGUAUGGCGCGCUUCCUGGGGAGAGUUCCAGGCGCGUGUCCCGGAGCGCGCGCCCCUGCCGCCCCCGGCCCCCUCUCAAUUCCAGGCGCGUAUGCCCGACAGCGGGCCCCUUCCCGAAACCCACAAGUUCGGGGAAGGAGUGUCCUCCCCCAAAACACACCUAGGCGAGGCAUUGGCACCCCUGUCCAAGGCGUACCAAGGCGUGGCCGCCCCGUUCCCCAAGGCGCGCCGGCCGGAGAGCGCACUCCUGGGCGGCUCCGAGGCGGGCGAGCGCCUUCUCCAGCAAGGGCUGGCGCAGGUGGAGGCCGGGCGGCGGCAGGCGGAGGCCACGCGGCAGGCCGCGGCGCAGGAAGAGCGGCUGGCCGACCUCGCCUCGGACCUGCUGCUCCAGUAUUUGCUGCAGGGCGGGGCCCGGCAGCGCGGCCUCGGGGGUCGGGGGCUGCAGGAGGCGGCGGAGGAGCGAGAGAGUGCAAGGGAGGAGGAGGAGGCGGAGCAGGAGAGACGCGGCGGGGAGGAGAGGGUGGGGGAAGAGGAUGAGGAGGCGGCCGAGGCGGAGGCAGAGGCGGAGGAGGCGGAGAGGGCGCGGCAGAACGCGCUCCUGUUCGCGGAGGAGGAGGACGGGGAAGCCGGCGCCGAGGACAAGCGCUCCCAGGAGGAGACGCCGGGCCACCGGCGGAAGGAGGCCGAGGGGACAGAGGAGGGCGGGGAGGAGGAGGACGACGAGGAGAUGGAUCCGCAGACGAUCGACAGCCUCAUUGAGCUGUCCACCAAACUCCACCUGCCAGCGGACGACGUGGUCAGCAUCAUCGAGGAGGUGGAGGAGAAGCGGAAGCGGAAGAAGAACGCCCCUCCCGAGCCCGUGCCGCCCCCCCGUGCCGCCCCCGCCCCCACCCACGUCCGCUCCCCGCAGCCCCCGCCCCCCGCCCCCGCUCCCGCACGAGACGAGCUGCCGGACUGGAACGAGGUGCUCCCGCCCUGGGAUCGGGAGGAGGACGAGGUGUACCCGCCAGGGCCGUACCACCCUUUCCCCAACUACAUCCGGCCGCGGACACUGCAGCCGCCCUCGGCCUUGCGCCGCCGCCACUACCACCACGCCUUGCCGCCUUCGCGCCACUAUCCCGGCCGGGAGGCCCAGGCGCGGCGCGCGCAGGAGGAGGCGGAGGCGGAGGAGCGCCGGCUGCAGGAGCAGGAGGAGCUGGAGAAUUACAUCGAGCACGUGCUGCUCCGGCGCCCGUGACUGCCCUUCCCGGUCCCGCCCCCGCGCGCCCCCGCCGCGCGCGCGCGCCGGCGCCCCCCUCCGUGUUGCCCGCUCCCCCUCGGUGUUUGCAUGCGCCCCGGCCCUGCCCCUUGGCCCUGCCCCUGUCCCCGGGCUGCGUCGGGACCUGCCAGACCCCCCUCCCGGGUCCUGAGCCCGAACUCCCAGAGCUCACCCGCGGGUGACCGGGGGCCAGCCCAGGAGGGCGGGUGGUUUGUGCGAGUUCCCUUGCCACGCGGGGCCCCGGCCCCAUCAAGUCCCUCUGGGGACGUCCCCGUCGGAAACCGGAAAAAGCAGUUCCAGUUAAUUGUGUGAAGUGUGUCUGUCUCCAGCCCUUCGGGCCUCCCACGAGCCCCUCCAGCCUCUCCAAGUCGCUGUGAAUUGACCCCUUCUUUCCUUUCUCUGUUGUAAAUACCCCUCACGGAGGAAAUAGUUUUGCUAAGAAAUAAAAGUGACUAUUUUAUUAGGA